AAGUCGCAGCUCCGGGCGCCGGCUCCCGGGACCCCGUGGGGCGGCGGCCGCGCGCGCGCUCUGCCCUCGGGCGGCCCUGCUCUCCCCCGCCCGGCCCCGCAACCCCGCAAUAACUUGGCUGGGCGGGGUCCGGCACUGGGCUAGAGAGGUCGAGCGCGGCGUCUUGAGCCGCUGGCGGGAGGCUGCUGCUUCCCCGCCUGCAUCAGUGCGGGUCCCGUGGACUCCUCGCCCCCGUCCCCGCGAGCUCGGGGCUCCACAUCAAGGAAAUCCUCAGCCCGGGAGUGGCUUCCCCAGAAACAGCAGCCCCAAGCCUCCGAGAGUCAGUCGGAGAAAAGGACACACUCAGGCGCCCUGCGACAGGGAUGCCCGUCCGACCUACAAGGAACGCCUCGUAAACCGGGGUGCAUGGGAGACCACGGAAAUAACACGUUCUCGCUGUUUCCAAGCUUUGGGAUAGGCAUCUCGACCCUCGCUCUCUACCCACGUUUCCCCCCCAAAUCCUGGAGAGGGAACCAGAACCAGCGCCCCGCUGCGGGGCGGGCCGGCCAGCGCACCUCCUGGGGGUCACACCGACAAAUCUGAAGCGGGUUUGCCAGGGGAGUGUACCCGUCUCCCCAGCCUGGGCCACCCGGUCCACAGGGAUUCCAUUUCCGGCCUUACACUCCGCUCCACGAUCUCAUCCAGGCGCUGCAGCUGUGCAGCUGCUCUACAGACUGCAGGGACCUGCUGAGACGAAUCCCCGGACGAGGAAAGGGGCCCCCCGCCUGCCCUACUGAGCCUUGCGCGCUGACCCGGUUCCUACACUUAACUUUUCCGGCUUCGGGUUUAAGACGCGUGAUGGCUGGACCGGCGGAGGAGGCGGGAGCCCAUUGUCCCGAGAGCCUGUGGCCUCUGCCUCCGCAGGUGUCACCAAGAGUGACCUACACACGAGUGAGCCCAGGGCAGGCUGAGGAUGUCACCUUCCUCUACCACCCCUGUGCCCAUCCCUGGCUGAAGCUCCAGCUUGCCCUCCUGGCCUAUGCUUGUAUGGCUAACCCUUCCCUCACCCCUGACUUCAGCCUCACGCAGGAUCGGCCCCUGGUGCUGACUGCAUGGGGGCUGGCGCUGGAGAUGGCCUGGGUAGAGCCAGCCUGGGCUGCCCACUGGCUGAUGAGGAGGCGGAGGAGGAAGCAGAGGAAGAAGAAGGCAUGGAUCUACUGUGAAAGCCUUUCAGGGCCUGCUCCCUCCGAGCCAACUCCCGGUAGAGGGAGGCUGUGCCGAAGAGGGUGUGUGCAGGCCCUGGCUCUGGCCUUUGCUCUGCGGAGCUGGCGGCCCCCUGGCACAGAGGUGACAUCUCAAGGGCCCAGGCAGCCCUCUUCUAGUGGUGCCAAGAGGCGGAGGCUGCGGGCUGCCCUUGGUCCCCAGCCCACUCGCUCAGCCCUGAGGUUUCCCUCUGCUUCCCCAGGGAGCUUGAAGGCCAAGCAGUCCAUGGCGGGAAUCCCUGGUAGGGAGAGUAAUGCCCCAUCUGUGCCCACUGUCUCCCUGCUGCCGGGGGCGCCUGGAGGCAAUGCCAGCUCCAGGACAGAGGCUCAGGUGCCCAACGGGCAAGGCAGCCCAGGGGGCUGUGUCUGUUCAAGUCAGGCUUCCCCGGCCCCUCGCGCAGCAGCGCCUCCACGGGCAGCCCGGGGCCCCACCCCACGCACUGAAGAGGCCGCCUGGGCUGCCAUGGCCCUGACCUUCCUGCUGGUGCUGCUCACCCUGGCCACGCUCUGCACACGGCUGCACAGAAACUUCCGACGCGGGGAGAGCAUCUACUGGGGGCCCACAGCGGACAGCCAGGACACAGUGGCUGAUGCUGUCAUCUCCAUUUCCAGGAGAGAUAACCAAGGCUCAGAGAGGUCAAGCAGCCUGCAAGUCACACAGCCAGUAAGCAGCAGAGAUGACUUCACACUUCUGUGCCUGGAACUCUCCGCUCUCGGGAUGGUCACUGCUCCUGCUGAUGCUCUCGGGGCUGCUCAUUCUCCAGCUCGUCUCUAUCCCAGUCUUGCUUGUAGGGUUCCCUGCCUCCCAUGCUGUGCUCCAGCCCGGGGGCUGCCUCCAUUCCCAUGCAGCAUUUCUACCCUCCAUGCCUCUGCCUCUCUUGCUGCACUCCCCCAUGAGGACUAGAAUCACCUGGCUAGGCUGCCUCCCCAGCUAGAUUGUGAGCUCCUUAAGGGCAGGGAUUGUGUCUCAGCUGCCUCUGUGCUCCCAGUGCCAAGAGCAGUAGCUGGCUCCGGGAAGGUGCUCAGUUAAUGUGCUGUUGAAUGGAGCCCAUAUUUGGGUGUAUUUACCAUACACAUGCACGCAUGCACACACAACCCAGGUAGAAUCAGACCAUAGAAGUAGGAGCCUUGGGGUCUGGAAGAGGUCUGGGUUUAGGAUCUGAGUCGCCCAGGCCUGGUUAUGCCCAUCUGCCCACACAGGCCCUUGGGGAGGAGAGCACCUCCUCUCUCCAGAUCCAGGCCAGCAGGCACAGCCUGGCAUGAGGACAUGGCCAUCAGAGGUGGCCACCAGGUGGCACCAGCAUCCAUCUUAUGUGCUGGGUGAGUGGCAGGGGGUGUCCCACACUGCCUCUCAGACGGAAGCAGAAACACCUCAUUCAACCAGCCUCAGCGCACGUGCCUAAUUCUGAGCACGCUAGAGGCCUAGCCAGCAGUCACAAAGUUAGUCACAUCCCUGAAGCCCACCCAUCUUUUCAGCGAAGAGCAGAGGCUUCUCUAAAGACAGUGGGGUCGGUGCCACUGGGACAGAACCCAGUGGCCCACCCUCCCAGCCGGAGGUAGCUUCUGUUUCUUUUUCUUUUUUUUUUUUUUGAGACGGAGUUUGGAGUUUUGCUCUUGUUGCUCAGGCUGGAGUGCAAUGGCGUGCUCUCGGCUCACCGCAACCUCUACCUCCUGUGUUCAAGCGAUUCUCCUGUCUCAGCCUCCCGAGUAGCUGAGAUACAGGCAUGCGCCACCACGCCUGGCUAAUUUUGUAUUUUUGGUAGAGACGGGGUUUCUCCAUGUUGGCCAGGCUAGUCUUGAACUCCCGACCUCAGGUGAUCCGCCCGCCUCGGCCUCCCAAAGUGCUGGGAUUACAGGCGUGAGCCACCGCGCCCGGCCCACAGGUAGCUUCUCACACCCAAGCCCUCCAUGUACUUGACAGUCACGGGGCUCAGGCUAUGCGGGCCACAUAUGGAGCUGACAUUUUUUACCUGCCUUGGGGCCCAGCAUUAGGGACUGAGGACUAAGCUGUGCCUCUAGUCUCUGGGGGGAGGGAGCAGGGUCCUAGGCCUCUGAAACCUGGGCUGGGAGCUCUGGGGGUCAGCCACCCACAUGGCAUCCAACAGCCUCUGGAAAGGGGCAUCAGGUGGGCACUCACCUGUCAGCCAUCUGUGGGAUGAUGUAAUGCCCAUUCUUGUGAUCUGAACAAAAAUAAAAAUGCCAAGUCACUCACUAGUGCUGGGUGGCCUCAGCAGCUGGGAGCCCACCUCACUGCCAUGAGCAGGGCUGGCACCCAGAAGUGUCAGGGGAAAGUGGGGAGGGCAGGCCACCCCCAAGAAUGCUGGGAGCUCGUGGGAGGAUGCAGGAUGCCCACCCCCACUCCCUAGCCCCAGCGAUGCUAUGGCCCAGAGCCUGCAGUAAUUUCACAGGAGCCAGUUGCCUAGCAACAUUGCUCCCCAGCCGCUCUGUCACCAUGGCACCUGCUGCCGGGUGCGUCCAGGUCCCACCUGCCCAGCCCCAGCCAGGCCUGUCACAGCCAGGCGCCCCCCAAGCUCUGCUCACCCGGCUUGCGUCCACAGAGGUAGAAGGCCAGCCGGUCAGUGAGCUCAUAUUGGCACUCAACCAGCCUUUCCGCCAGCUCAUGGUGCCCCGCCUGCCUGUGAGGAGGGGGUAUGGCUCAGACCUGCAGCAGCAGCCCUCACCCACACCCCCACCCACCCACACUGCACCCUUCAGCCGACCCUCACCUGGCAUAGUCAAUGGGUGUGCGGCCAUUAACAUCAGGGGAGCCAGGGUCAGCCCCAUACACUACAAGCAGCUCGGCCUGCAGUGUCUGUCCUGCCUUGGCAGCCACGUGCAGAGGUGUGGUGCCCUUCUCUGGGUGGAAGAAGUUGGCCUGGGCACCCAGGGAGAGCAGGCGCAGACAUGUCUCCAGGUUGCCUGUCCGCACGCUCGAGUGUAGUUGCUAAGAGGAGCAGAGUGUGCAGUGAAUACGCAUGUGCGUGAGGCGCACCUCCCCACCCACAAGCUGCACCCUGGCUGCCCCUGGGACACCUAGCAGCUCCAAGGAGGCCUGCCCAAACCAGACUAUGUCGGGAGGACAGAGGCUUCCCGCUAGGGGUUAAUGCCAAUUAAUAAACGCUGCCGUCAGUCACCAUCUA